AUUCUGCGGCCGAGGAUUACAUUUAUGCACGAACGGGCUUACUGGUUCCAGAUUCCCCACUUGGGCACAGGCAUAGGAGGCUUGUUUUCCAAAUUGCUGGUUUUAAUUGCACCUGCCUUUCAGAUUACCUCUGGGAAUCUGUGGGAGGAGCCGAGAGGGUGGAAAAUGUUUCUUAGCUUUGCAAAAGGAAGAAAACUUUGUCACCCAGCGGGAGACCUCAGCCACGAGUAACCCGGGGAGACACCAGAACCGGGACGGGCUUUGACUGAUUUGCCUACGAGGGUUCCGUAGGAAAGGACGCUUGAAUUCGGCGCUUCGGCGGCGGCGGCGGCCGCGCGAGUUCCCUGCUCACCCUCCCUCUCCGCGGAAGUCCCCACGAGGUGGCUUCAGGGUGUAACAGAGCGCGCGGCUCCAGUCCGAAGGCAGCGGCCGGGGGAGGGAAGGAGGGGACCGAACCCCCGAGGAGUUUCGCAGAAUCAACUUCUGGUUAGAGUUAUGGGAAGCGCGGUUAUGGACACCAAGAAGAAAAAAGAUGUUUCCAGCCCCGGCGGGAGCGGCGGCAAGAAAAAUGCCAGCCAGAAGAGGCGUUCGCUGCGCGUGCACAUUCCGCCCGAGACACCUGCGUGGGACCUGCCUCCACCACUCCGGGCAGCCGCCUGGGGUCCACGGGCAGCCUGAGCUAGCAGCAGGCCUCACAUCCGGCCCUCAGCUCUUUUACACCAUCUUGACGACCUGAGCUCCUUCGCCAUGCCGCUCCUGGACGGAGACCUGGAGGGUUCCGGAAAGCAUUCCUCUCGAAAGGUGGACAGCCCCUUCGGCCCGGGCAGCCCCUCCAAAGGGUUCUUCUCCAGAGGCCCCCAGCCCCGGCCCUCCAGCCCCAUGUCUGCACCUGUGAGGCCCAAGACCAGCCCCGGCUCUCCCAAAACCGUGUUCCCGUUCUCCUACCAGGAGUCCCCGCCACGCUCCCCUCGACGCAUGAGCUUCAGUGGGAUCUUCCGCUCCUCCUCCAAAGAGUCUUCCCCCAACUCCAACCCUGCUACCUCGCCCGGGGGCAUCAGGUUUUUCUCCCGCUCCAGAAAAACCUCCGGCCUCUCCUCCUCUCCGUCAACACCCACCCAAGUGACCAAGCAGCACACGUUUCCCCUGGAAUCCUAUAAGCACGAGCCUGAACGGUUAGAGAAUCGCAUCUAUGCCUCGUCUUCCCCCCCGGACACAGGGCAGAGGUUCUGCCCGUCUUCCUUCCAGAGCCCGACCAGGCCUCCACUGGCAUCACCGACACACUAUGCUCCCUCCAAAGCCGCGGCGCUGGCGGCGGCCCUGGGACCCGCGGAAGCCGGCAUGCUGGAGAAGCUGGAGUUCGAGGACGAAGCAGUAGAAGACUCAGAAAGUGGUGUUUACAUGCGAUUCAUGAGGUCACACAAGUGUUAUGACAUCGUUCCAACCAGUUCAAAGCUUGUUGUCUUUGAUACUACAUUACAAGUUAAAAAGGCCUUCUUUGCUUUGGUAGCCAACGGUGUCCGAGCAGCGCCACUGUGGGAGAGUAAAAAACAAAGUUUUGUAGGAAUGCUAACAAUUACAGAUUUCAUAAAUAUACUACAUAGAUACUAUAAAUCACCUAUGGUACAGAUUUAUGAAUUAGAGGAACAUAAAAUUGAAACAUGGAGGGAGCUUUAUUUACAAGAAACAUUUAAGCCUUUAGUGAAUAUAUCUCCAGAUGCAAGCCUCUUCGAUGCUGUAUACUCCUUGAUCAAAAAUAAAAUCCACAGAUUGCCCGUUAUUGACCCUAUCAGUGGGAAUGCACUUUAUAUACUUACCCACAAAAGAAUCCUCAAGUUCCUCCAGCUUUUUAUGUCUGAUAUGCCAAAGCCUGCCUUCAUGAAGCAGAACCUGGAUGAGCUUGGAAUAGGAACGUACCACAACAUUGCCUUCAUACAUCCAGACACUCCCAUCAUCAAAGCCUUGAACAUAUUUGUGGAAAGACGAAUAUCAGCUCUGCCUGUUGUGGAUGAGUCAGGAAAAGUUGUAGAUAUUUAUUCCAAAUUUGAUGUAAUUAAUCUUGCUGCUGAGAAAACAUACAAUAACCUAGAUAUCACGGUGACCCAGGCCCUUCAGCACCGUUCACAGUAUUUUGAAGGUGUUGUGAAGUGCAAUAAGCUGGAAAUACUGGAGACCAUCGUGGACAGAAUAGUAAGAGCUGAGGUCCAUCGGCUGGUGGUGGUAAAUGAAGCAGAUAGUAUUGUGGGUAUUAUUUCCCUGUCGGACAUUCUGCAAGCCCUGAUCCUCACACCAGCAGGUAAAAUGCUGGUUUCUGACCUUUGCCAUCGGCGUCUAGGAAGGGUGGGAGGUAGAACAGGAAGUGCAGCAUUUAAACCAUCAUUUCUCCACCCACCUACAGAUCAAGGCUUUGAGUAUAUUACUUUGAAACCAUUUUCGUUUUCUCUUCAGUUGGGAAGUUUAAGUGUUCUGCGUGAGUGAGGAAAGUGUAUAGAACGUAUUCGAAGUUAAGAGCAUCCUAUCAAGGUCCAGUGGCCCCCUAAAUGACUUGGGAGCCAUUGCCAUGUUCAUCAUAACCUUUUCCACUGAAAAGACCUCUUCAAUUGUGCUUUGUGAGAGAACUAGUGACCAGAAACAUAGAGGGAACGUCACUGGCUUCUAUUUGAUACCUUCAUCUUUCCUUAAAGAGAAAAAAAACUUAUAUUUUGAGUAGAUAAAACAGAAUACCUAAACACAAACUUUUAUUCAUUAAUAUUGUACAGAAAUCACAUUCACUUUCAGAUAGAGUGUGGUUAAACUCAUUUUUUGACAGAUUCACUUUGAGCAAGCCUUCAGAGUCUCAGACAGUGAGGAGCAGAGAGAACGGGAGAGGGCUUUAGACAAGAGGAGCUGGCCUUCCUCUCAUUUCACACACUCAGUAGUAAGAGGUGGGCUUGAGAGUUCUUAAAACUGCCAGCCCUCCCUUCCCUCCUCCUCUUCCCAUCCCUCCACCUCCCCAGCCCCAGUCAAAUAUGAACAACCCAGCCUUUGUCAGGGCCACAUGGACCCGAUGUGGGAGCAAACAGCAUGCCCUUUGAACUCUCAGAAUCCAAUAUUAAACGGUGUGUGUGCUACAGUAUUGAUUUCUCUUUAGUUCAGAAAUUUCAGUUAAGACUAGUUUUUACAAUUAAGUCUGUAACCCAAAAAUACCUACCCUAAAGGAAUCUUCACCACCUGCAAGAAACAUGUCUUAUUCGCUAAAUGAGAACACCAAGAGAAAUUCCAGUACAGCAGUGAUUUUUCCGAGGUGGUCCUCAGGCCAGGCAUCAUCACCACCACCUGGAAUUUACUAGAAAAUGAAAUGUUCAUGUUGGGGCCCCGUCCCAUAUCCACUGAAUCAGAAACUCUAGAAAUGGGGCCUGGUGCAGUCACUUGCAAACUUCAAGUGUUUAAAAGACCUGAAUCUCACAAUAGUCUCUAUAAUCAUGAAACAUUAAGAACUAAACGAAUGUUAAUGCCAUAAAACUGGGAAUAAUCCAAAUAUCUUUGAAAAGAAGAAUGGAUAAAUUGUGUCACAUUCAUUCGAUGGAAUACGAUACAGGAUUGAAAACGAACAGUACAGCUGCAUUCAACAGUGGAGGAAUCUCACAGGCAACAUUGAACAGAGGGAGCCAGGCUCAUCCAGACCAUCAUUAAAUUCAUAUAAAUUUCCAGGCAGGCAUAACUGCACAGCACAUUUGUGCUAACUAGAAAAGGCCUCUUCUCUGGGCAGAUUUAUCCCCACAGGUAUAUAGCUUGGCACCUUCAGAAAAAGAUGCCCCGUUUCCAGCCCUGGACCACGGGACACAGUCUGCCCAGCGGGUCAGGCUGAAUGUCAGCUCUUGUCUGUCUCUUUGGGCAUUACAAAAAGAGUAAACAAGUCAAGCGAUUCAUCCUCUCUGUUUCUUGAUAUCUCAAACCAUAAGAAUGAACGGUUGUGCUGGAUGAGUUCAAAUUUCCAUCCAGAUUUGGUAUUUCAAAAAUUCUAAGUCAUUGCAAUGCCCCUCCCAUCACUGCUGGUGCAGAGAGGAAUCUAUUUCCAGCUGGAAUUUGGAAUGUAUGUUACCAUAGAAAUUGUGCCGUGAAGAUGGGGGUAGCUGGGUUGGAAUUCCUUAUGAUACAGUGUAUACAACACGAUUUGUUGAGGAAAACAUUCCGUGUUACUAAUAACUGGAUUACAAGUGAACUUUUGGAGUGGAACUCAGGGAGCGCCUGCAUCUGAUCAACAAUCGCAAGUGAGGAGGCCCCCACCGUGAGGCCAAGUCCCAGCUGUCCCACCCGAGCGCUGUCUGAAUGUAAGCAAGUCGCUUCACCUCCUUCAGCCCCAAUUUCUUCAGUAGAGAAGGAGCCGGCUGAUACAGGCCCGUCUCCCUCCUAUGUUGCUAUGAAAAGAGCUGAAAGCCGUGCACAAAAGCCAUGUGUGUGCAAUGAGGCGCAGUGCCCGGGACCUGCACUGUUAGGUGGUUGUCCAUGGAAUAGUCAGUAAGAGGCAGUUUGAUGAAGUGUCUGCUGUUACUCGAUUAGAAGGUACUAGUGGUGAUUCUUUUCAUCGGGCAAUGGCCACCGUUCCCCAGAGGGGUACUGGUUCAACACAAUAACACUUUCUCUUUCUCAAAAAAGUUUUUAGCAACAGUUCAUUGUCAAACUUAGACUGUCCAAAUGAACCCAUGUGUGCGUGCAUCCAGUGUGUGGGCAGUCUGAUGCCAGGAGCUACGGUGUUUCAGCCACACGCUCUAAUAGAUUGCCGAUCUCUUUCAGGGGUCUAGCGUCUGGUGAAAAAUUAGGAGAGAAGCUCCUGUGAUGAGAAAAAUAGUAGCUCUCCCUGCCAAUCCACUGUGGAAUGUCCUAGCCAGAUACUUGUUAGGUGCAAUUAUCCUUCAGAAUAUUUAUAAAGGUUUUUUUUUUGUUUUUUUGUUUUUUUUUUUUUUAUUUGAGACGGAGUUUCACUCUUGUCAACCAGGCUGGAGUGCAAUGGCAUGAUCUCUCGGCUCACUGCAACCUCCACCUCCCGGAUUCAAGCGAUUCUCCUGCCUCAGUCUCCCAAGUAGCUGGGAUUACAGGCGCCCGCCACUACGCCCAGCUAAUUUUUGUAUUUUUAGUAGAGACAGGGUUUCACCAUGUUGGCCAGGCUGGUCUUGAACUCCUGAUCUCAGGUGAUCCGCCCGCCUCGGCCUCCCAAAGUGCUGGGAUUACAGAUGUGAGCCACCGCGCCCGGCCUAAACCUUUUUUUAAUACAUAUUUGUAAGAGUGCACAACUGAAAUACUUCACACCUUCACUAAAACAUACCUACAUAUUUCUUAGUAAAAUUUUUUAAGAGUGGAAUUCUUUUUUUUUGUUUUCCAAGUUAAAUCUGACAUAUUUAGAAUGACAAGAUGUUACGUGGAUCCAAGCUGCCCGAACGAUUGGGUGGGAGAUGGGAGCUUGGGCCACCUGCUCCUUCCCACAUCGCCCUCCUCCGAAGCCUCUGGAUCAUCCUCCUAAGGCACUGCCAGACACAGGUAGAAACCCCUGGGGUAGAGAACCCUGCUGUUACCAUGAGCUUUGAAACUUUCAUCUUCCAUCCACUGACAGGUGCCAAACAAAAGGAGACAGAAACGGAGUGACCGCCGUGAAUGUAGACGCCCUAGGAGGAGAACUUGAACAAAGUCUCUGGGUCACGUUUUGCCUCAUGAACACUGGCUGCAAGUGGUUAAGAAUGUAUAUCAGGGUUUAACAAUAGGUAUUUCUUCCAGUGAUGUUGAAAUUAAGCUUAAAAAAGAAAGAUUUUAUGUGCUUGAAGAUUCAGGCUUGCAUUAAAAGACUGUUUUCAGACCUUUGUCUGAAGGAUUUUAAAUGCUGUAUGUCAUUAAAGUGCACUGUGUCCUGAAGUUUUCAUUAUUUUUCAUUUCAAAGAAUUCACUGGUAUGGAACAGGUGAUGUGGCAUAAGGUGAGUGCACGGUAUGUUCAGAUCACAGUGCCUUAUGUCCGAAUACAGCAAUAUGUCACCGCCGCAGCCGGGGCGCACGCGUGUGAAACAACACCGAGCUUGAAUGUGGAAGUCUUUGAACCUUUUACCAAAUCAGUUUGUUUUCUUUAGAUUUGUCAAAAAGUUGUAAUUUGAAUAUAAAUAAUUACUUUAAAAUUGUAAUGACACUUUUACACGUAAGUGUUUUGUUCUGGGCUACCGUGUCAACGAGGCUGCUUUACAACAGCUUUAUUUAUUUUUACUUUCAUGCAAUUUUUUUACACAUCUUUUGGUGGAGUAAACUUCACCACAUCCAUGAAUAAACUCUCAGUUAUUUUGAAAUGGCAAAUUUCUCAUUAUUUAAGUUUGGAUCUGGAAAGGACAUGACUUCUGAAAUAGCCGCUGCUGGGUUUUAAAAGCUGAGGUCUCUCAAAGUGUGGAGGAGACGUUGCCGUCAGGCGGGAGCCAAGUGCCGGGAAGAUGUCUAUUUUUUUUCUUGUGUAUUGAAAUGUAAAAUCAUGAUGUUUGUUAUGACUGCUGAUGCGAUUGUUUUUGUAAAUUUUAUUGUGGCAUAUACAGUAUUGUCAUACAGUUGAAGAGAAACAAUGUUUCCUAAUGUAAGUGCUCUGAAAAUGUUGACACUGUAUAUAUAUAUAUGAGGAUAGUUUGUUUUUUUUUUGUUUUGGGUUUUUUUUUUUCAGAUUGAAAAAUUAAAAUAGAUCCUACUAUCUA